GCCACCAUGCCUGGCCAAUGUAUUUCUAUUUAUUUAUUUAUCCCUCAACAGUCCUCCCUCCAAUUUAAUAUAUUUCUUGGCAGAGGAUAGUAAAUGUUUCCAUGGAUGGAUUCCUUGGUGGUGGUGAUGGUGGUUUGUUUUUUUUUUUUUUUUGAGGCAGAGUCUUGCUCUGUCACCCAGGCUGGAGUGCAGUGGCACGAUCUCGGCUCACUGCAACCUCUGCCUCUCAGGUUCAAGCGAUUCUCCUGCCUCAGCCUCCUGAGCAGCUGGGAUUACGGGUUCGUGCCACCACGCCCGGCUAAUUUUUUGUAUUUUUAGUAGAGAUGGGAUUUCACCACGUUGGCCAGGCUGGUCUCGAACUCCUGGCCUCAGGUGAUCCACCCGCCUUGGCGUCCCAGAGUGCUGGGAUUACAGGCGUGAGCCACCACACCUGGCCGGUUGUUUAUAUUUAAUUGUCUUUUUUUCACUAAUGAGGACCACCUUGUAAAUUCUGGGCAUUUUCAGAGUUUUCUCUUCCAUGUGAAUUGCUCCAGCUAACUUAAUAUUAGUUUCUCAAGGGUUUGUGUAGACCUGGCUUUGUCUCUUUCCAUCUGUUUCUCUCUUUCCCUUUAACGUCACUUGCCUGAGGUCUAUAAGGCCCUUUAAGGUUGCCAGCCCAGAGCCAGAAGAGAUUGGUGUCCCUGAAGUUAAGAAAGCCACCUUUGCCUACAGAUGGUGUUCACAGUGUUGGUGUGGAGUCACAGCUUGACUUUUGGGGGCCCCAGGAGAUGUUGACCCAGCAGGGCAUGGCGCUGCAGAACUACGACAACAAGCUGGUCAAAUGCAUAGAGGAGCUAUGCCAGAAGCAGGAGGAGCUGUGCUGGCAGAUCCAGCAGGAGGAGGACAAGAAACAGCGGCUGCAGAAUGAGGUGAGGCAGCUGACAGAGAAGCUGGCCUGCGUCAACGAGAAGCUGGCCCGCGUCAACGAGAACCUGGCACGCAAGAUUGCCUCUUGCAGUAAGUUCUACCAGACCAUCGCGGAGACGGAGGCCACCUACCUCAAGAUGCUGGAGAGCUCCCAGACUUUGCUCAGUGUCCUGAAGAGGGAAGCUGGGAACCUGACCAAGGCUACAGCCUCAGACCAGAAAAGUAGUGGUGGCAGGGACAGCUGACCAGACCAUGGGCAGGGCCUGCCUCUGUGCGCCCCUCAACUCAGCCCCAGCAAGUCUGUCCACAGAGCGUCUUCUUCAUGGCAGCAGCUGCCUUCUUUCACUGUCUCAGGUGCUAAGAGGGGCAGCUGCCAACCUCCACUGGCAUCAGUGACAAGCCCGGGGCACAGCCUGUGGGUCCUGGCUUUGUGCUCACACAGGCUAUGGGGAGGGUGGGCUCUAGGUCAGCUCUGCAAGGGGCCUGUCUCUGCGGCACCCACACUCCUGGGCUGCCAGGGAGGUCCUGGUUGUAGUCUGAGCACCAUGGAGGUCCCCUCAGCCAGCAGAGGCCCAGGGCAGGGGGCAGGGGUUCUCCUUCAUCCCAGAACCCAAACCUCAGGGCUCACCCCUGUGGCCUGUGACUGUCAAUAAAGAUUAUCUUUGUAAAAAUAAA